UGUUUUUUUUUGGUUGGUGUGUCUGCUGUCUUGUAGAUUUUGUCAACACACUCUUUCUUCUUUCCCUUUGGCCUGAUCCCCAAGAUUUGGGGCUGAGAUUUAUGCCAUCUGCCUCUGCCAUGAUCAUUUUCAACCUGAGCAGUUACAAUCCAGGACCCUUCAUUCUGGUAGGGAUCCCAGGCCUGGAGCAAUUCCAUGUGUGGAUUGGAAUUCCCUUCUGUAUCAUCUACAUUGUAGCUGUUGUGGGAAACUGCAUCCUUCUCUACCUCAUUGUGGUGGAGCAUAGUCUUCAUGAACCCAUGUUCUUCUUUCUCUCCAUGCUGGCCAUGACUGACCUCAUCUUGUCCACAGCUGGUGUGCCUAAAGCACUCAGUAUCUUUUGGCUAGGGGCUCGCGAAAUCACAUUCCCAGGAUGCCUUACACAAAUGUUCUUCCUUCACUAUAACUUUGUCCUGGAUUCAGCCAUUCUGAUGGCCAUGGCAUUUGAUCACUAUGUAGCUAUCUGUUCUCCCUUGAGAUAUACCACCAUCUUGACUCCCAAGACCAUCAUCAAGAGUGCUAUGGGCAUCUCCUUUCGAAGCUUCUGCAUCAUCCUGCCAGAUGUAUUCUUGCUGACAUGCCUGCCUUUCUGCAGGACACGCAUCAUACCCCACACAUACUGUGAGCAUAUAGGUGUUGCCCAGCUCGCCUGUGCUGAUAUCUCCAUCAACUUCUGGUAUGGCUUUUGUGUUCCCAUCAUGACGGUCAUCUCAGAUGUGAUUCUCAUUGCUGUUUCCUACGCACACAUCCUCUGUGCUGUCUUUGGCCUUCCCUCCCAAGAUGCCUGCCAGAAAGCCCUCGGCACUUGUGGUUCUCAUGUCUGUGUCAUCCUCAUGUUUUAUACACCUGCCUUUUUCUCCAUCCUCGCCCAUCGCUUUGGACACAAUGUCUCUCGCACCUUCCACAUCAUGUUUGCCAAUCUCUACAUUGUUAUCCCACCUGCACUCAACCCCAUGGUUUACGGAGUGAAGACCAAGCAGAUCAGAGAUAAGGUUAUACUUUUGUUUUCUAAGGGUACAGGAUGA